ACUGGCGGCGGCAGCGGCGGAGGCGACGGUGGCGGCUCUCGGAGCCGGCGCGAAUCCGGCCCCCGCAGCGGGACCCGGGCAGGUCUUGACGAGCCCUGCCCGGGCCGACGCAUGCGGAGGAUGGAAACACUUGCCCGGCAAUGUCUCUGGGCCGCCUCCUUCGCAGGGCCUCCUCCAAAGCCUCGGACCUCCUGACCCUCACCCCCGGUGGCAGCGGCAGCGGGUCCCCCUCUGUCCUGGAUGGAGAGAUCAUCUACUCCAAGAACAAUGUCUGCGUGCACCCGCCGGAGGGGCUGCAGGGGCUGGGGGAGCACCACCCAGGUUACCUGUGCUUGUACAUGGAGAAGGAUGAGAUGCUGGGAGCCACCCUCAUCCUGGCAUGGGUCCCCAACUCUCGCAUCCAGAGGCAGGACGAGGAGGCCCUGCGCUACAUCACACCCGAGAGCUCCCCCGUUCGCAAGGCACCCCGCCCUCGGGGCCGGCGCACCCGGAGCUCAGGAGCCUCCCACCAGCCCUCCCCGACGGAGCUGCGGCCUACCCUGACCCCCAAAGAUGAGGACAUCCUGGUGGUGGCCCAGAGUGUUCCAGACCGCAUGCUCGCCAGCCCUGCGCCAGAGGAUGAGGAGAAGCUGGCGCAGGGCUUGGGGGUGGAUGGUGCCCAGCCAGCCUCGCAGCCUGCUUGCAGCCCCUCCGGGAUCUUGUCGACGGUCAGUCCGCAGGAUGUCACCGAGGAGGGGCGGGAGCCGCGGCCCGAGGCCGGGGAGGAGGAUGGCUCUUUGGAACUGUCAGCCGAGGGCGUGAGCAGAGACAGCUCCUUUGACUCAGACUCAGACACCUUCUCCUCGCCCUUCUGCCUCUCGCCCAUCAGCGCGGCGCUGGCCGAGAGCCGCGGCUCCGUGUUUCUGGAAAGUGACAGCAG